CCUUUGGAGUCCUGGAGGCGGCAGCGUUGUUGUCCAGCCCGACGGUUCCCGAGAUGUGGGCCCCGCGCUCCGAGAAGAGGCCUGCGCGGGCCAUGGCGGCCCCCCGGUUUGGUGGCCCCCGGCGCGGCGGCGCGCAGCACGAGCUGCUGGAGAAGGCGGCGCGCCUGGAGCGGGGCCCCCCUCCGCGCGGGGAUCCGGAGGCGGUCGGGCGGCGCGCGGUGGCCGGCGACGGCGGCUCCUGCUCUGGGUGCUGGUGCUGGCGGCGGCUGUUCCGCGGCCCGCGCAGGAAGAAGCUCAGGCAAGCUCACGCGCGCGCAGGCAAGGAGGCCCCGGAGCGCGGCCUGUGGGGCCCCUCGAGCCUGCAGAGGCUGCUUCAGAGGCUGGCGACGUGGAGGCGGCGCUACCUGCGGCGCAAGGAGCGGCCGGACCGGCUGGAGGAGAUCCCGCUGCUGGUGCUGGACCGCGCGCAGGGCGGCCACGAGGCCGCGGCCGGACCCCAGAGCAGCGUCCCCGGGCGGCCCGCGCAGGCCGCCCCCGCGCGCCAGCCCCGCCGCCGGUCAGCCACGAGGAGCCGGUCCCCCGUUGCGCCCCCUGUGCACGCUCAGGAUUGUUUUUUUCUUUUUGGUCAACAAAAGCAAUAAAUGAAAGUAACCCCAGCACCGUAGGAAUGAAAGCACAUGCAAUGUUGGGGGGAUGUGCAUGGAAACCAAGGGUUAUCUUGAGGUUCGCAGCGAGCUAAACGAGCCGCGUCCUCCUCGCAGCCUCUCUUUGGUCCGAGGGCCUCGGAGCAGUAACUAAAGCCUGCGGGUGCCGCGGAGCCCUGGGUUCCCCCCGCUGCGCAGUUGCUGCGGGCUGGGAAGCGCUGAAUCGGGGGCGGAUUGUCUCUUCCUAAACACUGCAGGGGAGAAGGUGGGAAACGGUUUUCAAUCUCUGCAAUGCCUUUUUUUUGAGACAGGAGAAAAAAAAAAAAAACCAACUAUGUUGCCCGGGCUGGACUCAAACUCCUGGGGUCAAGCGAUCCUAAGCCUCCCAAGCGUUGGGAUUGCAGGCGUGAGCUACCACGCCCCGUCAAAAAAAUAAAAAAAUCGUUUAAAGCAGGAUGCUGAGCUUCACAUCCCACUUUGAAGUGAGCGAACUCUACUUUUAUGCUUUUGUUGACAGGCAUUUAGGAAGGGUGGCUUGGGGUGGGGGUGGGACAGGGGAGUUUGGAAACCAGGGCUAGACUUAGAAGAACAAAGGGAAAGGACUCCUGGAGGCUCCCAGAUGGGUCUUGAAUGUCUUCCUUUUCCUCAUCAAUAAAAACCUGCUAAUGAUA